CUCCUCCCCCGAAAGCCGCGACCGAGUGGCCCGGUCCGCGCGCGCAGCUCGCGCCCAGCGCUCUCCAGCCGGGGUGGCGGCGGCGGCGGCGGCGGCGGCGGCGGCGGCGGCGGGGGAGGGGUGCGGCGGGGGAGGGGAGGAGGCCUGGCCCCGCGGUCGCAGCCGCCACCGCCCGCCCCGACCUCCCGGACCGCCGCGGGGCCACGGGCCCGAGCCCCGGAUUCGCGCUCCGGAUUCGCCUCGGCUCGGCCGCGCGUAUAUUUGCCUUCCCUCCAUGAUCUCCAACACUAUCCGAUAAAGUAGAAGCAACUGAGGUACCGUGAAAGAGAAAGGAGCUGGAACUGAGAAAAAGCAGAGAAACUGAAAGGCCAACGUGGGAGACAAAGAAGAGCCUGAAAGAGCCAAAUCUUACCUUCUGGACCAUGGAUUCGGACGGAGAGCGCGAGGACUCGGCGGCUGAGCGCGCCCGACAGCAGCUAGAGGCGCUGCUCAACAAGACUAUGCGCAUUCGCAUGACAGAUGGACGGACACUGGUCGGCUGCUUCCUCUGCACUGACCGUGACUGCAAUGUCAUCCUGGGCUCGGCGCAGGAGUUCCUCAAGCCGUCGGAUUCCUUCUCUGCCGGGGAGCCCCGUGUGCUGGGCCUGGCCAUGGUACCCGGACACCACAUCGUUUCCAUUGAGGUGCAGAGGGAGAGUCUGACCGGGCCUCCGUAUCUCUGACCACGAUGGCGCUUACCUUUCAGACUUCAUUAAACUUAUGACCGAA